ACUCGCCCUCCAGCUUCUGCCCUGCCUGCUGUGUGCGGAGCCGUCCAGCGACCACCAUGGUGAGGCUCGUGCUGCCCAACCCCGGCCUAGACGCCCGGAUCCCGUCCCUGGCUGAGCUGGAGACCAUCGAGCAGGAGGAGGCCAGCUCCCGGCCGAAGUGGGACAACAAGGCGCAGUACAUGCUCACCUGCCUGGGCUUCUGCGUGGGCCUCGGCAACGUGUGGCGCUUCCCCUACCUGUGUCAGAGCCACGGAGGAGGAGCCUUCAUGAUCCCGUUCCUCAUCCUGCUGGUCCUGGAGGGCAUCCCCCUGCUGUACCUGGAGUUCGCCAUCGGGCAGCGGCUGCGGCGGGGCAGCCUGGGUGUGUGGAGCUCCAUCCACCCGGCCCUGAAGGGCCUAGGCCUGGCCUCCAUGCUCACGUCCUUCAUGGUGGGACUGUAUUACAACACCAUCAUCUCCUGGAUCAUGUGGUACUUAUUCAACUCCUUCCAGGAGCCUCUGCCCUGGAGCGACUGCCCGCUCAACGAGAACCAGACAGGGUAUGUGGACGAGUGCGCCAGGAGCUCCCCUGUGGACUACUUCUGGUACCGAGAGACGCUCAACAUCUCCACGUCCAUCAGCGACUCGGGCUCCAUCCAGUGGUGGAUGCUGCUGUGCCUGGCCUGCGCAUGGAGCGUCCUGUACAUGUGCACCAUCCGCGGCAUCGAGACCACCGGGAAGGCCGUGUACAUCACCUCCACGCUGCCCUAUGUCGUCCUGACCAUCUUCCUCAUCCGAGGCCUGACGCUGAAGGGCGCCACCAAUGGCAUCGUCUUCCUCUUCACGCCCAACGUCACGGAGCUGGCCCAGCCGGACACCUGGCUGGACGCGGGCGCACAGGUCUUCUUCUCCUUCUCCCUGGCCUUCGGGGGCCUCAUCUCCUUCUCCAGCUACAACUCUGUGCACAACAACUGCGAGAAGGACUCGGUGAUUGUGUCCAUCAUCAACGGCUUCACAUCGGUGUAUGUGGCCAUCGUGGUCUACUCCGUCAUUGGGUUCCGCGCCACACAGCGCUACGACGACUGCUUCAGCACGAACAUCCUGACCCUCAUCAACGGGUUCGACCUGCCUGAAGGCAACGUGACCCAGGAGAACUUUGUGGACAUGCAGCAGCGGUGCAACGCCUCCGACCCCGCGGCCUACGCGCAGCUGGUGUUCCAGACCUGCGACAUCAACGCCUUCCUCUCAGAGGCCGUGGAGGGCACAGGCCUGGCCUUCAUCGUCUUCACCGAGGCCAUCACCAAGAUGCCGUUGUCCCCACUGUGGUCUGUGCUCUUCUUCAUUAUGCUCUUCUGCCUGGGGCUGUCAUCUAUGUUUGGGAACAUGGAGGGCGUCGUUGUGCCCCUGCAGGACCUCAGAGUCAUCCCCCCGAAGUGGCCCAAGGAGGUGCUCACAGGCCUCAUCUGCCUGGGGACAUUCCUCAUUGGCUUCAUCUUCACGCUGAACUCCGGCCAGUACUGGCUCUCCCUGCUGGACAGCUAUGCCGGCUCCAUUCCCCUGCUCAUCAUCGCCUUCUGCGAGAUGUUCUCUGUGGUCUACGUGUACGGUGUGGACAGGUUCAAUAAGGACAUCGAGUUCAUGAUCGGCCACAAGCCCAACAUCUUCUGGCAAGUCACGUGGCGCGUGGUCAGCCCCCUGCUCAUGCUGAUCAUCUUCCUCUUCUUCUUCGUGGUAGAGGUCAGUCAGGAGCUGACCUACAGCAUCUGGGACCCUGGCUACGAGGAAUUUCCCAAAUCCCAGAAGAUCUCCUACCCGAACUGGGUGUAUGUGGUGGUGGUGAUUGUGGCUGGAGUGCCCUCCCUCACCAUCCCUGGCUAUGCCAUCUACAAGCUCAUCAGGAACCACUGCCAGAAGCCAGGGGACCAUCAGGGGCUGGUGAGCACACUGUCCACAGCCUCCAUGAACGGGGACCUGAAGUACUGAGAAGGCCCAUCCCACGGCGUGCCAUACACUGGUGUCAGGGAAGGAGGAACCAGCAAGACCUGUGGGGUGGGGGCCGGGCUGCACCUGCAUGUGUGUAAGCGUGAGUGUAUGCUCGUGUGUGAGUGUGUGUAUUGUACACGCAUGUGCCAUGUGUGCAGAUAUGUAUCGUGUGUGCAUGUACAUGCAUGGGCACUGUGUGAGUGUGCACGUGUAUGCACACAUAUACAUGUGUGUGGGUGUGUGUAUUGUAUGUGCAUGUGCCAUGUGUGCAGAUGUGUCAUGUUGUGUGUGUGCAUGUACAUGUAUGGACAUUGUGUGAGUGUGCAAGUGUGCAUGCAUAUACAUGUGUGCGAUAUUUGCUGCCCGUGUGUGUGCAUGUAUAUAUAGACAUACAUGCCUAUGUUGUGUGUGGUGUGCAUAUGUGUGAACACACACGUGUAUACAUGCAUGCACAUGUGCUCGUACAAUGGGUGUCCACAUGCACGUGUAUAUGUAUAUCUGUGAGUGUAUAUACAUGCAUGCAAUUGUGUGUAUGUGUGUUCUGUGUGUGCGUUUGCAAGUAUAUAUGCACAUGUGUAUAUGUACAUGUAUGCCUGUGUGACGUGUGUAUAUGUGAGCAUGUGUACGUGUGUGUAUACGUGUGUUGUGUAUAUGUGUGUGUCUGUACCUGUUUGUGUAUAUGUGUGUGAUGUGUGCUCGUGUGUGUGCAUAUUCAGGCAGGUGUGCAUUUGUGCAUGCCAGUGUGUAUGUAUGUGCGCAUAUGGACACGCAUGGACACGCAUAUGGACACAUAUGGACACACAUAUGGACACGUGUGGAUAUGUGUGCGUACACGUCGCUGGGACACAUGCCUGCCACUCGGGGCCCAGCUGCCCUCUGUGUUUGUCCUUGCCACAGUCACGGGGUGCAUGUGCAGAGGGGAGCAGACCACUGGGGACGUGCUGUGCCCUGCACGUGCCCGGGGGAAGCGGAAGCUGCAGCUGGGGUGGGGGCAGCACCUCUAUGCUUCAUCUCUGUGGGUGGCAGGAGACAAAAGCACAGGGUACUAUCUUGGCUCCUGGGAGCGACUCUUGCUACCCACCCCCACCCAUCCCCUUCCCCUUGGUGUUGACCUUUGACCUGGGGGUUCCCAGAGCCCUGUAGCCCUCGACCCGGAGCAGCCUCUCGGAAGCCGGAGUGGGCAGUUGCUGGCGAUUCUGAGAAAACUUGGCCGCAUCCACCGGGGCCCUGCCUCCAGUCGGCCGCUGCCGAGUCUCUGCGUUCUGGCCGCUUCCCGGCUUAAUGAAUGCCAGCCAUUUAAUCAUUGCUCCUGCCACCACAAAUAGAUGAGCAGUUAAAUAAAACUCAACUUGGCAUAAUUCAAGGCAAAUACCACUCUGUGCAUUUUCUUAAGAGGACAUGAGCUGUGUGAAUUUUUAGCCAGCCUUUGGAAAAGAUGGGUUACAGGGUAACUCAACCCUGGCUGCCAUCCUUGGGCACUGUGUGUGUCCAGGGCACCUUGGAGGACCGUGCAGCCCCCAGAAGCUUCCAGCUCCCGCACCACUCAGUGAAGCCCAGCCUGGCGCCUGCCCUGCCCCCGUCACGGGAUGGGCCCCCAUUGGGGUUCAACAUUCCAUCGCAGCCAAAGGCAGUCGGCACUUGGGACAUCUGCUUCCACGGACAGGUCACCUCCGCUUUGCACGGAAGAAUCUGGAUGCUUACAUUAAACUGGUGUUCUGAGAGUUCCUACGGACAGGUCACCUCCGCUUUGCAUGGAAGAAUCUGGAUGCUUACAUUAAACUGGUGUUCUGAGAGUUCCUACGGACAGGUCACCUCUGCUUUCCAUAGAAGAAUCUGGACGCUUACAUUAAACUGAUGUUCUGAGAAUUCCUACAGGCAGGACUGAAAGCCUGGUGUGUGCCAGUAUGAUGUUCCACCCACAGAAACCUGGUCACAAUCGUCCCUUCCAGCACCCCAUCCAGCAGUGACUGCACACACUGAGUCCCCUACCAGCCCCUUUCACCCUGCUGACUGUCACUGGGCCCUGGGAUGCGCAAGACUCCACAGCAGCAGAGGUGGGGGGACAUAUCACAGCCUCUGCCCCCGGCUGUGAUGCCACCGAGGGGCUCGCCUGCUGAUGGCUUCAACAGGGUCUCACCUCAUCUUUUCCUGCUCUUUGGCCCUGGAUCGAGAAAAUUUCCAUCAGUGCCCCAUUAAUAUGCUGCCCUGUGGCAUCUGCCCAGGAGGCCCUGCCAGGCGUGCACAGGUGUGCAUUGGUGUACCCUGGCAUGCACAGGUGUGCACUGAUGUGCCCUGGCAUCCAUUGGUGUACCCUGGUGUGCCUGCCAUAGGACCCUGGGCGGGAGCUCCCAUCUCAUCUACAUCUCCUGAUUCAUGCGUUGUUUCAUAGGUUUCAAUGUCUCUGUAAAUGUGGUAGAAAUGCAGGCUUUAUGGGCAUAAAGUGUACAUUUCUAAAUAAAUCCCUUCUAUUGAGUAUGCUCACCCUAGAAGUUACUGUUGUCCAGACGUAGAGGGAUGAGUGAGCCAGUGACCUCAGACGGGAUGGUGGGGACGGCAGGUCCAGCUCCUGCCUCCUCCUGGGGGGUCUGGCUUUGGGGGCUUGCUCCGAAGAGGCCAUGGCCCAGGCCUGUGGCCUCACAAUGGGGACCAACCAGCUCUUCUCAUCUUCUUCCCUCACACUUCCUCUCACUCAAAUAAGAACCUUCCAAAAAUGUGUCCACCUGGGCCCCUGCCCUGGGACUCAUGGAUUUGGAGUUGUGGCCACACGGUUGAGGGGUGCAGUGUCCAGUGGAAUGGGGCAAUUGCGGGCCUGGGGGCCCUUGGCCUGUCCGUGGCGGGAGCAUCUGCAAGGAGGAGCCCCAGAGUCCAGGGAGCACUGUGGGGAGCUCCUUAGAGCUGAACUCACCCGGCGUCAACUCAUCAACCCUCCACCCAUGGACAGGGGUGCCCCCAGCACAGGAGAGGACUCAGCCCUCUGCCCCCACGCACGGUGGGUGCCUGUCACCCUGUCCUGCCCAGCGGCCCGAGGGCAGCAGUGGGUGUGAGGGCAGCCCCCGGCCUCCCAAGAGCAGCUGAGAGGAUCCCUGCGGGAAUCCGGGCUUCGGGUGCAUGCGAUCUGAUCUGAGUUGUUUCUGACAGUGACAGAGUGACAAUCUAUAAGUAUCUCAAGAUCAAAUGGUUAAAUAAAACAUAAGAAAUUUAAAACGA